AAUUCCUGUCCUGGGCGUACGUCAAGAUGGCGGCGUCUGUAUUAAACACCGUGCUGAGGCGGCUUCCUAUGCUAUCUCUCUUCCGAGGUUCUCACAGAGUUCAGGUUCCCCUCCAGACUCUUUGCACCAAAGCUCCCUCUGAGGAAGAUUCUUUGUCCUCAGUUCCCAUUUCUCCUUAUAAGGAUGAGCCCUGGAAAUAUCUGGAAUCAGAAGAAUACCAGGAGCGAUAUGGUUCUCGCCCCGUCUGGGCUGACUACCGCCGCAACCACAAGGGUGGUGUACCCCCACAGCGGACUCGGAAGACAUGUAUUCGUCGGAAUAAAGUUGUUGGGAAUCCCUGCCCCAUCUGUCGAGAUCACAAGUUGCAUGUUGACUUUAGGAACGUGAAGCUCUUGGAGCAAUUUGUCUGCGCCCACACGGGUAUCAUCUUCUAUGCUCCAUACACAGGAGUCUGUGUGAAGCAGCACAAGCGGUUGACCCAGGCCAUCCAGAAAGCCAGGGAUCAUGGUCUCCUCAUUUACCACAUCCCCCAGGUUGAACCACGGGACCUUGACUUCAGUACCUCUCAUGGGGCUGUGAGUGCUACUCCGCCAGCCCCCACCCUGGUCUCAGGUGACCCCUGGUACCCAUGGUACAACUGGAAACAGCCACCGGAGAGAGAACUGUCUCGCCUUCGCCGGCUUUACCAGGGUCAUCUCCAAGAAGAGAGUGGCCCCCCACCUGAGUCAAUGCCCAAGAUGCCCCCUAGAACACCAGCGGAAGCCUCCUCCACUGGGCAGACAGGCCCUCAGAGUGCUCUGUAGGAGCUGUAGACUGGGAAGAGAGGCCAGGCGUGGUGGCUCACUCCUGUAAUCCCAGCACUUUGGGAAGCCAAGGUGGGCUGAUCACUUGAUCCCAGGAGUUUGAGACCAGCCUGGGCACCAUGGUGAAACCUCGUCUUUACCAAAAAAUACAAAAAUUAGCUGGGUGUGGUGGUGCACACCUGUAGUCUCAACUAUUGGGGAGGCUAAGGUAGGAUCACUUGAUCCCAGGAGGCGGAGGUUGCAGUGAGUUGCAGUCACACCCCUGCACUCCAGCCUGGGUGACAGCUAGACCCUGUCUCAAAAAAAAAAAAAAAGACUGGGAAGAGAGCUAGAGGGACUAGGAGAUAAUGUGUAUGUAGGUUUAUGUGAUGGGAUAUCACCCUGAAGAGUUGUGUCUUUUGUGGCCAGUGACAAAUCCAGGAAAUGAAUGUUGCUGAUAGGGAUAAAUCUUGAGGCUGAGGGCGGGUGGUACAGAUGUGUAUGGGAAACCCCAACCCCUAUAUAUUGUAAAUAGAUGGGCUGGGCUAAACAUUGUUGCCGUUUCAUACUUCUACCAACUCAGCUUUUACACAAUAAAGCUCUACUGUCUCUGGUU